AGAUGAAUGUGGCUGUUGAGAGCGGCAAUAAUCCAGAAUGGCUACUCUGAUCUACGUUGAUAAGGAAAUUGGAGAACCAGGCACCCGUGUGGCUGCCAAGGAUGUGCUGAAGCUGGAGUCUAGACCUUCAAUCAAAGCAUUAGAUGGGAUAUCUCAAGUUUUAACACGACGUUUUGGCAAAACAUACGAUGCUCCAUCAGCCUUACCUAAAGCUACCAGAAAGGCUUUGGGCACUGUCAACAGAGCUACAGAAAAGUCAGUAAAGACCAAUGGACCCAGAAAACAAAAACAGCCAAGCUUUUCUGCCAAAAAGAUGACCGAGAAGACUGUUAAAACAAAAAGUUCUGUUCCUGCCUCAGAUGACGCCUAUCCAGAAAUAGAAAAAUUCUUUCCCUUCAAUCUUCUAGACUUUGAGAGUUUUGACCUGCCUGAAGAGCGCCAGAUUGCACACCUCCCCUUGAGUGGAGUGCCUCUCAUGAUCCUUGAUGAGGAGGGAGAGCUUGAAAAGCUGUUUCAGCUGGGCCCCCCUUCACCUGUGAAAAUGCCCUCUCCACCAUGGGAAUGCAAUCUGUUUGCAGUCUCCUUCAAGCAUUCUGUCGACCCUGGAUGUUGAAUUGCCAGCUGUUUGCUAUGACAUAGAUAUUUAAAUUUCUUAGUGCUUUGGAGUUUGUGUGUACUUGUAUUAAUAAAGCAUUAUUUGUUUAACAACAUAAUAAAUACAUAAAUAUAAA